CAUUUAUUGAGAGCCUACCAUAUGCUAGAUUGUGUGUAUUGAAGUACCUCCUCUACUAAGCCAAGAGCACCUCAAAGGCAAGACCAUUUCCUAUUCCCAUCUGUGACAGGUAGUAGAAUCUGACUGGCUGAGCUUGGAGCUGGACUCUGCACCUUGCUAGCUCUGUGUCCCUGGGCAAGUUACUAACUUCUCACCUGGAAAGUGGAGAUCAGGACACCACCUCCCCUCUAGAAUUCUUGUGAGACCUAAAUAAGAUAACACACAUAGCACAGGGCUUGCAGGGCACACCAUGAAUGUUAGCAAUUGUUCUGACUGUAUUUAUGAGAUCAGUGCCUGGCGCACAUCUGUUUUUUGAAAUACGGUAAACAGUAAAUGCUCAACAAAUGGUAGUUCUUUUUCAUAAGCUUUCUUUAAAUAGUCUUGCAGUUCACAUGUGACAGAUCAUGGUGGUAUGUUCCACUGGGACUGAUCCCAAGAAAUGAAGAUGAGGUUUUCUAGAGUUUAACUCUGAAAGUUCCCUUCAAACAAGUUUCUUCAUUUGGUAGCUGCACACCGACGGGGGAGUGGGUGACGGAAUUUGGACCAACUCAUUCAGUGUCUUAGGGUAUUAGUGUGUUCAUGUAGUCAUUUGCCUCAGCUAAGCCCAACCUCCAUGAUCUUUAGCCAUGCUGAGCUGGAGAGAAAGCAGUACCCGAGAAUGUUCAUGGAGCUUGCUGCCUGAACAUGGACCCUACACAUGCACCUGCUAGGGGAGGAGAGUGAUGGUGUGUGUGUAUGUGUGUAUUGUGGGAAGUGGUGAGGUGGUAAUACAGCUAGGAGAGCAAGAUAAAGAACAUGAUGACUCAGGGGUCCUUUAUUUUACGUGGCAUUUCCAAAAUGUGGCUUCUGAUGACACAACUGCCCCACAUUCCCAGCCCGUCUCAGGUAUACCUCAGGCUUUCCCUUCUUCCCAUUGGCUUUUUCUUUUUUACUUAGAGAGAUAUUUAUUAAGAUCGAAAUCCACUAAAGAAAACACAAAAAGUAGCAAGAAACCACUUUAGUGAGAGGACUUUUUGGGAGAGUGUAUGUGAUAGUUAAUACUGAGUGUCAACUUGAUUGGAUUGAAGGAUACAAAGUAUUGAUCCUGGGUGUGUCUGUGAGGGUGUUGCCAAAAGAGAUUAACAUUUGAGUCAGUGGGCUGGGGAAGGCAGAUCCACCCUUAAUCUGGUGGGCACAAUCUAAUCAGCUGCCAGCGAAUAUAAAGCAGGCAGAAAAACGUGAAAAGGAGAGACUGGCCUAGCCUCCCAGCCUACCUCUUUCUCCCGUGCUGGAUGCUUUCUGCCCUCGAACAUCAGACUCCAAGUUCUUCACUUUUGGGACUCAGACUGGCUCUCCUUGCUCAGCAGCUUGCAGACAGCCUAUUGUGGGACUUUGUGAUCAUCUAAGUUAAUACUUAAUAAAGUUCCCUUUAUAUCUAUCCUAUUAGUUCUGUCCCUCUAGAGAACCCUGACUAACACAGUGUAUGUAUGGUUUUAUUUUUUAUUGCUUCCAAUAUUUUCUAGACCUGCUCAAUGUGGUGUUGGAGAGCUCAGUUUGGCCCUGGCAAGACACCAAUGCAGGCUCUUGGUUCUCUGGGCUCCUUGUUUUUCUUCUGGGCCCAGGAACCUUUAGUGUUAGUGACAUGGAGCUGGUGGGCUUGGCUGUUGGAUUUAACUACUCUCUUCAUAUGUUCUCUGAAGGACUUUUCAGAUAUUGAGGUGAAUCUUUAACCUUCUAAAUUCUUCAGGUAGCUUGGCUGGUCACCAGCCUUGCCUUCCAGAACAUGUAAGGCCUGAAUAUUUUAGUCUCUGCAGGGGUAGAUGGAGUCACAGGAGGAGGAAUUGACGAGCUAGCUGGGUUUUCAGGUUUUCAGUGUAAAUCCAGGAACAUGGGCCCUGGGGCCAGGCAGUGUUAGAGAUGAUUUAGUCUAACCUUUUCAUUUUACAAACAUAGAAGCCGAGCCCAGAGGGGUUAAAUGACUUGCUUUUGUUCACACUGCUGGGAGCAGCACCACGGCUGGGAUGCAGGCCGUUGUGACUUCUGCUUUGAGGUUCUUUCUAUUCUCUGCUCACACACCUAGACUUGAUGAGGUAGAAAUGAAACUCUGGCUUCUUAAUCAAUUCAUAAGCAUUACCUACUCCUCUUACCUUUUUUAAAAUGGCAUUUGCCUCCUCUUUAUUUUGUUCAAGUUUCUUCUUCUUCUCCUCUUCCAUGUAAUAUGUGUGCAUGGAAGCAAAGUAUAUCAUAUGCCAAAGAACUUAAGUUAAAUAUUAUCAUUUCCCCUGACCACUCACUAAAGGCAAUCUUCUCUAAAUUGUUUUUUGUUUGGUUUUGUUUUUGUUUUUGGAAGUUACUGCUAAACUCAAUAACAUGCUUCUGUCUUUGUUUCUUUAUUUGUUAGCUGUUGUAACAUCUCUUAAGUCUCUGCCUUGAAAGAUGCAGAUUCAGCUCAGUUGUCCUGUGCCUCCUCUACCUCUGCCUUCUCUCAUUACUUUAUUCCAUUAUUGCUUUCGCUAUUGGCUGUACACUUAAACCUUCCCUUUGUGGCCCAUCAACUUUCCAUCGUUUUGCGUAAGAUGGAGUUCUAAGCUCUCUUAGGAUCCUUUUCUUGCCCUCCUCUCUUCUACAUUUCCACCUUUGGCAUCUGCAUAGUUACUUCCACAUUGUUAAGUGAUUUUCCUCUGUAUUUUGUCCUGCAACCUCAAUGAUAUCUUCUGUGCUUUUGGUUAACUCUAACAGUGAAAAAUGAGUAAAUUGCAUUCAUAAUUAUGACUAUGCAAUUCGUGUUUGUUGCUUGACCAAAUCAUGUGUUAGGAUCCUUCUCUGGGGGACCUGAGGUCGUAACUCAAGGGCCUCUCAAAGAAGAAUAUUCCUAACGUCAAUGUCGAAUUGGUUAACUUUUUAAAAAACUUCAUUGGUUGCUUAAAAUUGUUUGACCAAGGUUGAUAACUCUGUCUGUCUCUCCUAAAAAGGUUUCUGUCAACCUUUCCUCUUUCUCCUAUCUCCCUCCCAUCCUUUACUUCACAGUGAAAUAGUCAAGUACCACUGAGUUUUCUUAGACUUAGGAGCUGUCAGAAUUUAAGGGUCUAGUCUGUGAGAGGAGCUCAGUCAAUGGUGAGAUCGAAUCUUUGGACCUCCUUUGGACCACCGGAAUGAAAUCACACGUUCCCUACAAUAACAAGAGAAGCUGUUAUUUUGCAAAAUCGAUGGAUAUUGCUAAUGAGUUUAAAUUUUCUUUGUCUUUAUUUAUUUUUGGUCUUUUCUUCACAAAGGAGAAUGUCAGCAUAAUAGCUGCUGUUUGAUUGAUGAAUCCUGUUGUGACUGAUAAUAAUGAUUCUGAUGCUUUGUGUUGAACCAAAAUAAUAAAAAGCCCGAGGGUACUUAUAAUAUGCCUAGCUGAGUUUUGAAUCAUGGACAUCUGAAGGCUUUACAUAAUAUGACACUAGAAACAGCUGGUGAAGGAAAAGCCUGGAAGAUCUCAAAAAUUAUCCCAGUUCUAAAGCGUGAUACCUGCUGUUCUAAACUGCCAUUUGGAUGCUUGACUCGCAUAUGAUGCAAAAUAUUGAAAUAGAUAAUUUACCAAGCUUGCAAUUUCUCAUGCUGAAGAAAAUAUGCAAUUAGGAAAUGCCCAACAUAGAUUUAGAAAAGAGUCAUUGCAACAACUCAAGUGGUUGAUGUUAAACCAUAAUUUUCCCCAGAUAAUGGAUUGCCACAGGAGCUGAAUCCACUUGGCUGGAUCCUCCACCUGUCACAAGUUUUCACCCCCUGCUCUCUGUCUGUUUGUGGGUUCUAGAUGGGAGAAGAGAAACACAGGGUGGCAGGAGAUAAGCACUGGCUUUCCAGAUUUGUCUUAAGUCUUGGCAAAAUUUAUACAACGGAUUAUAACAUAUAUUCUCUGCAAUUCAUGUCUUUUUGAAAUAGUAAUUUUCUUUCUGAUGUGAUCGGGUGUUUGGAGUGGUUGGUGAUGAAGUAGAUGCAUAUCUUUAUGGCAUUAUAACCUGGAGGCAGAGGAAGCCCUGAAAUGUGAUUUAUGAGGAAUCCAAGAUGAAUUUGGAGCAGGAGAGGCCGUUUGUCUGCAGUGCCCCAGGCUGCUCCCAGCGCUUCCCAACAGAGGACCAUCUGAUGAUUCAUAGGCACAAACAUGAAAUGACUUUGAAGUUUCCUUCAAUAAAAACAGACAAUAUGUUAUCAGAUCAAACUCCGACCCCAACGAGAUUCCUGAAGAACUGCGAGGAGGUGGGCCUCUUCAGCGAGCUGGACUGCUCCCUGGAGCACGAGUUCAGGAAGGCUCAGGAAGAGGAGAGCAGCAAGCGGAAUAUCUCGAUGCAUAAUGCAGUUGGUGGGGCCAUGACGGGGCCCGGAACUCACCAGCUUAGCAGCGCUCGGCUGCCCAACCAUGACACCAACGUUGUGAUUCAGCAAGCCAUGCCGUCGCCUCAGUCCAGCUCUGUCAUCACUCAGGCACCUUCCACCAACCGCCAGAUCGGGCCUGUCCCAGGCUCUCUAUCUUCUCUGCUACAUCUCCACAACAGACAGAGACAGCCCAUGCCAGCCUCCAUGCCUGGGACCCUGCCCAACCCUACAAUGCCAGGAUCUUCCGCCGUCUUGAUGCCAAUGGAGCGACAAAUGUCAGUGAACUCCAGCAUCAUGGGGAUGCAAGGUCCAAAUCUCAGCAACCCCUGUGCUUCUCCCCAGGUCCAGCCAAUGCAUUCAGAAGCCAAAAUGAGGUUGAAGGCUGCAUUGACUCACCACCCUGCUGCCAUGUCAAAUGGGAACAUGAACACCAUGGGACACAUGAUGGAGAUGAUGGGCUCCCGGCAGGACCAGACGCCACACCAUCACAUGCACUCGCACCCGCAUCAGCACCAGACACUGCCACCCCAUCACCCUUACCCACACCAGCACCAGCACCCAGCACACCAUCCUCACCCUCAACCCCAUCACCAGCAGAACCAUCCACAUCACCACUCCCAUUCCCACCUUCAUGCACACCCAGCACAUCACCAGACCUCGCCACAUCCGCCCCUGCACACCGGCAACCAAGCACAGGUUUCACCAGCAACACAACAGAUGCAGCCAACCCAGACAAUACAGCCACCCCAGCCCACAGGGGGGCGCCGGCGAAGGGUGGUAGACGAGGAUCCGGACGAGAGGCGGCGGAAAUUUCUGGAACGGAACCGGGCAGCUGCCACCCGCUGCAGACAGAAGAGGAAGGUCUGGGUGAUGUCAUUGGAAAAGAAAGCAGAAGAACUCACCCAGACAAACAUGCAGCUUCAGAAUGAAGUGUCUAUGUUGAAAAAUGAGGUGGCCCAGCUGAAACAGUUGUUGUUAACACAUAAAGACUGCCCAAUAACAGCCAUGCAGAAAGAAUCACAAGGAUAUCUAAGUCCAGAGAGUAGCCCUCCUGCUAGUCCUGUCCCAGCUUGCUCCCAGCAACAAGUCAUCCAGCAUAAUACCAUCACUACUUCCUCAUCGGUCAGCGAGGUGGUAGGAAGCUCCACCCUCAGCCAGCUCACCACUCACAGAACAGACCUGAAUCCGAUUCUUUAAAAUGCACCAUCAGACCUGGCCUCCAAGAAGAGCUGUAGCGUACCAUGCGUCCUUUCUUUUAAGGGCAUUUUUAGAAUUAACUCAGACCUGGAAGACUCCUCAGUUCUUCAAAGACUGGCUUUCAUUUUUAUAGUUAUUAUGGAAAUGUUGUCUUUUAUACUUAGUUAUAUAAGAAAAAAGGGAGUUAUGCAAUUAAUAUCUAUCAGCUUGGGAAACGCUUUGGUGCUUUUCUCCAGUUUUCUGGUACCAGUUACUUGUUUAUAAACUGAACCUUUUCUGUAUAUAGCCAUGGUUUCAUUCUUAUCAGUCCAACCCUUUGCCUGAAACAUUGAAUCUUGUUAAACCACAGCUUUUAGCUAAAAUGAGGUAUACCUAGAUGUCAAGUAAGACAGAUCCAAGGUAACUGGGUAGGAAAUCUUUUGACAUCUUAACUCAUGUUGAGUUUGUGCUGUGGUGUCACCAGAAUUCCAGAUAAACACACAGCCUUUCCCAUACCUUUUUUUUUCUUACUAUAAAAUAUUAUAAGAUCCAUUGAUGUCCAAAUAAUACCACCAAGCAUCUCUUCACCUCUCCUCCUCUUGGUCCACUUGCUAAUGCCCAGUUUUCUUCUCCAUUUCCACUUUUUCUUAGGCUCCCUAUUUACUAUUCAUUUUGACUUCCUUCUGUUUUAUUUUUUUCCCUUUAGCAUUGCAUGUGAAUAAGAAAAUAAUGUUUAAAGAAAAAAAAAAAAAAGCAAACCUCCAAAACGUGGACCUAACCAUUGCUUCACUUACACUUCACCCACAGCUGGAGUUCAUUCAACUCUUGCUUUUCACAAAAUAGUAACCAGGAGAUGUUUAAUGUGCCUGAUUUAAUGUUUUUAAUAAUCACAGCAAAUGAAAGGUGGUUUAGUUAUAAGUGAAGCAUGGUUGAAUACCAGCUGGGGAGACACUAGGGAAGGGAGCUUUGUAAGCCUUGAUUGCGAAAGUCCAAAUUUUGAUGUGGGGCUAUAACAUGACACCCUUGGAUUGCGACUGGUUUUAUACGGCCUGCCUAUAACGUUGAAAAUCCAUGUACUACAUAAUAAUUCAGAAGGGCUCUAUUCACUACACAGAUUACAUUGUUCAAUCAUCAGCUGCUAAUAGCCUAAGAUUUAUUUUUUUUUUUUUCUUAAGCCUAUGGAACCGGCUUUGCUGUUCUGGGGGGUGAAAAUAGACUAACUACUGGAGAAACAAAGAGAGAAAGAAAACCCAGUGUUUCCAUAGGGGCACUUUUAGCCUUCCCACAACAGUUAAGCACUCUUUGACUGCUGAAGGAACCCCAUGGAUGAGGUGCAGGCUACUUCACUCUUUUUUUUUCUUUUUUGAGACAGAGUCUCACCUAUUGCCCAGACUGAAGUGCAGUGGUGCGAUCAUGGAUCACUGCAGCAGCAUCCUCCGAGUUCAAGCUAUCCUUCCACCUCCGCCUCCUGAGUAGCUGGGACCACAGGUUCACAUAACCAUGCCUGGCUAAUUUAUUUUUACUUUUAUUUUAAAAUAAAAGAUGAGGUCUGUCUUAUGUUGCCCAGGCUGGUCUCAAACUAUCCUACUUCUUCCUCCCAAAGUGUUGGGAUUAUAGGUGUGAGCCACUGCACCCAGCCUACUUCACUCUUCUGAAUUAUUCUGAUUUAUUUUCAACAACUUUUGUGAACUUGCCCGUGAUACAAAGCAGAUAGUCCCUGAACCACAGUCGUGCCUCCUUGAAACAAGCCAUUCUACUGUGCUAAUGUUUUAAUAUCACAUCUCACAAAUAACAGGGGUGAAUGUUUCUCUCUAGCAAUCUAGGCAGGUGCUGGUGUUUCAUCUCCAUUUGAAUGCUUGACCUCUUAAUGUGUGUGUGUGUGUGUGUGUGUGUGUGUGUGUUCAUGGGUUUUAAAAGAACAGUAUUUUACAAAAGGUGUAGCUUUUAUAAGAGUGCAGAAAAGGGAAGGAUGUGUUUUUUUCUCUCACUAUAGUAUAAGAAUCUAUUUUGGAGAAAAAAAGAAAAUAUGAGGGUCUCGAAGCAUGAUUUUUAUAUAACUAGUUUCAGUUUUAUCUAAUAACUUACUUUUUAAAUCAAUAUUUAUCAACAAUCUUUCCUUGUAUGCAGUGCUUUCAAAAGAUGGUUUUGAGUGUCCAGUGAAACUUAUGACUUGGAUAUAUGGUUGAAGAAUCAAAACAAAAGCAAAAAAAAAAAGCAAAAAAAGAAAAGAGAAAAAAAGAAAAAAUGCAAAUGGAAUAAUUUUCUAUUAUAUUUUAGACAAACAUAUCAUUUUCGAGUAUUUUAAAUACUGAAUUCAUAGUUGUUGUUUUUUAAAUUCCAACAGUAACAGCUGAAUGGUUUAAUCUGACUGGCUUCCUAAGAAAUGUUUAAGACUCAGCUUUAAAAAGAAGUUAACAUUCAUAUCUCUGUUUUGAAAUCAAAAAUCAUAUUUCAAAAUUCUUUCCUAGGACCAUCUAUGUGUCUCCCCUCCCCUCCACAAAAAGGAGAAAGAGUGCAUUAAAAUGUUUAGUUGGGUUUUUUAAUUUUUAAUUUUUAUGUUAUGUUUUGCUUUGUUUUAAGUAAACAAAAAUUUUUCUUUCUUUACUGCAUGCAUAGCACUUAAUAAAAUGGAUUUUUAAAAAAUCCACUAGUAAUAUCAGAAUGUCCAGGGAGUGACUGUCACUACAAUGAUGGUUUAGUUUACUUCUGUUCCACCUUUUGAUUGAAAUAUUUAGUUGUUAGGCUGAAAGCCUCGGCAGUUAAGAACUUGCCUGAGUUUUCUUCGUUCAGCAACUUGACAGUUUGACUGAUGUGCAUUAUAUAUAGCUCAAUUAUGUCUGUUUUUUAUGCUAAGUAGGAAAACCAACCACACACAUUAGCAAACCGGCCUCAACAUAUAAUUAGAAUAAACUGUCUUCUUGUUCUACUCAGGGCCUUUAGGUGUGUUCAUUCACGGUAUGGAAAUACAGUAAAUGAAAGAUUCCAACUAGUUGUCAGUGCUUCUUGAAAUUCCAAACAGAAAGAUACAUUGGUCAAAUCCAACACUUGGCUUAUCAAUAUUAAGUCUUUUACCUAAAGGCCCAGCCGUCACCAGACAACAGAAUAAUCAAUCUGCCUGAAAAUCCCUCCUCCUUGUCCUACACUUUUUGCCUGUUUGGGAGAAUAUCUUUGUACUCCAUUCUCCUCCCUCAGCCAGUUACUGGGUCACCCAUCCAUGUGUUCAUGAAUCAAUCAUCACGGCCUGCAGAGCACCUGUCCUAAGGAGGGAAAAUCCUGUCACACUGCCUCUCCCCAUUCGUGUGUGGUUUUCUUGAUCGGUGAGAUCUGUCUCUGAAGUCACUGCCAGCCUCCCUGGGAACGUCUAUAGUGCCUCCCCUGCCUUAUGUGAUGGGAGUUAACAACUCAGAUAAGUACACCUGAGAGCAUUUCUAUCAGGUAAACUGUCACUUAAAUGGAGGUGUCCACAUCUUAAUUGUUUCUCCUUGACACAUUUCUCAAUCCACGAAGCCAGGAGAGGUAGAGUGAAAAUCCCAGCCAUGGAUGAAUGUACUAAUUUGAAAGCCAAGUGUUAAGUCGGAUGUUUUCCCGUUACACUACUACUCAGCCCUCUCCUGCGGCCACAUCAACGGAUGCAAGUCACAGUCUUAACACAGCCUGUGGGAGACAAGCAGUUUGUGUGCUCACAGUAUAUAUUAUAGUAAUUAGGGUGACUUAGAGCAAAUACUCUUCAGAUCCUAUGUAGUCAGUGAAACAAAAUGGAGAGCGUAUUCUGAUAGAAGGACGUCGACGGUGAAUGUUCUGGUGGUUGUUGCCUGUUAAGUAAACUUUAGUGUGUAAGUUGAGUUUGUCAUUAAAAUCAUAAACCAGCUGCGGUAACAGACAAGCCUUUGGCUGGGGAGUUUUAAGCCUCGGUAACUGCUAUAAAACUAGCCAUCCAGUUAGGAUAGAAUGUGUUUCUUUCUGGUUAAAAAAAGGAAAAACCAUCUAAGAAAAUAUAUAUGUAUGUAUGUGUGUAUACAGUGGAAUUCAAAGGACCAAAGCAAAAUUUGAACAGGAAUCUAUUAAUUUAGAAUUUUAUAAGAUAUUUAUUAAUAAAUGUUAUUUUUAAACAUUCCAUUUGAACAGUAUUCUGUAGGAUCUACUUGUUUUUAAAGUGUUAGUCCAUAAUAAACUACUAUAGUUAUGUGUAUUUUCAUUUUUCAGGGUUUCAAAUGGCUAUUCUCCAUCAUUUGGUGGAAAUGUUUGCUUAGAUCUCUGUGCAUAGACAUUUCAAGGAUUUUUAUUGCUCUGUGAGUUAUUUUUUAAUCAACAUUCUGAACAGUUUUUUUUAAACAUUUAUUUCUGUGUGUUCAUUUUUAAAGUAAGCUCUUUCAUUUAGGAAGCAGAGUUCAGCUAAAGGGAAUCAGUAACUCUAACUGGAACAGCUUUCUUGUAGAAGUGUAAAAACAGCUUCAUCUCUGCCUCUCUCCACCCCACCCCAAUUUCCUAGAAAGCCUUGCACUAUUCAGCUCCCUUAGUGCUUUUUGUCCCUUCCCGAACAAUAUGCAGUAGCUUUAAGCCAUUCAAGCUCCAUUAUGCAGUAUAUCUGAGAAGGGAAAGGAAACAACCCAUUUAAAUUUGAAUAAAACCGUGCCUAUGCGAACAGUAGCAAUUUAGAAUCUCUUUUCUGCUUUUAAAAUAAUUUAUAUUUAAAAAUUGCACUUUAGCUUUUUGAUCCCUUUGUAUUUCUCUUAUUCUCUUUCUAACCUCUUCUCUGUCCUCAAACUUGCCUUUGCUCUCCUUUACAAUACCCCCCACCCCUCCUCCAAGGCUCUGAGCGGCAUCAUUUAAAAUACUUUACAGAUAUUUGCACCAGGUACAUUUAUGUGCGUCCAUUGGUAGCACAGCUGAGACCUGUGUCUCACAUCAGCCUAGGUGAAGCCUACUACAAGAAUGCCAAGGAGAAGAGCCAGUACACUAUAUGGUUUAUACUCUUUAUCCCUUUAUUCAUAGCAUGUUUUUUAAAAAUGUUAUAUUAUGCAACAGAUGUGAGGCAGCAGCUAAGCUAUACUUAAGAAUUUUCUCUCACCUUCCAAACCAAAGUGUCCUGAAUAAGCCAGGAGACUUAUUCUUUUGUGCACCCUGGUGCACAUCUGACUGUUGUCCUAGCCAUAGACUCUCUGAGGCCACUGAAAGAACAGUGGCCCUAUCGAUUUCAUUCCUAGGUCUCAAAAAUACAAUGUUGCCUUGUAACAUAAUUAGGGACAGCACCUCUAUUUCACAAUUAUAAUCUAAGGUAGGAUAAGACGACACAGCAGCAAUAAACUUACAAGUAAAAUUCAAUACCAAAACAAACACAAAGAAAUUUAAAAAACAAAAAACCUAGCUCAUCAUGUUGUGAAAAUGAAAAAGUGAAUGUCCAUUCAAAAUAUUUUACUAUUUCUUGUGGAGUUUUUCAGUGAUGUAAUGCUUGUAGCCAAAUUGCUUAAAGAGUGUUUAUAUAUUUUUUUCCUUAUAAAUUGUCUAUUUUUUAAAAAAGCUAUUUAACCACAGCUGAAGUGGGGGGUAAGGCCAAAUUGCCAACACUUGUUAAAAGAUUAAUACUCUUAAGUGGCACUCUGAUACCUUUCCAACUUGUCAUCAGAAAGGAAUCAAUAAUUACCAACUGUUGUAUUUAGACCAACUUACAAUAUCUAGCUCAUUAGAAGCCAGGAUCUAGAAAGCUCCUUCUAAGCCAUUUAAGAUAUUCUUACAUUGAGCUUCAUAUUAUAGAACUUUAUAGGAUUGGAUAUUUUACAAUAGAAUAAUUUAGCCUCAGGACUGAGAAUGUGGAAGCUGAAUAAAUUAGCUUUAAAUACAUCAUUAAAAUCUUAUGCACAAUAAGCUCAUUAGAUUCUAGUUUUCUCCUUUAGAAUACCAAUGCCACAGACACUACAGGAGAUAAUGAAAGGUAUCAGUUGUGUUGAGUGGAGGGAGUUUAAGAGAAAGGACCCUUCCCAACCAGCAGCCAGUAGAAAAUACAACCUACUCACCUUUUUCCCUUCUAAGUUCUGCUAAAUCACAUCUGCCUCAUAGAGAAAGGAAUGUUGCCUUUGAGAACUGUCUUGGAGAACAGAUAAGCUUGAAAUGUUCUCUCUAGAGAGGACAUAGGGUUUGGGAUCCUCUGAAAAGGCCCAGAAAAAUAGCUCAGUUCAAAUACAAUGUUCUAGGACAAUUGGAAUAUAAAUAUUGUCCAAAAAUAUAAUUAAAAGAAAAAAGUUUAGCACUGUGUAAAGUAAGUGUUAACUGAGGAAGUCCCAAAAAGGUGCUGUCACUUUAAGUUCUGGACUUGGGGUUCUUUGUAUUUGUAAACAGCAAAGCAUUUGUGUUUGUUUGUCUAUUUGUAAAGCAACCACCUUCCUUAUUGGAAGGAGAAAAAAAGGGGUACAUACAUGUAAAUACUUGCUGCAGCAUUUAAUAUGUUUAAUUUUGUGUUAAGCUUUUUGUUGCAUCGUGAACACAUUUAUUGUUACCAAUGGACAAUGAGUUCAUUAAGACUGUUCAACUAGGUCAGAUUUUUACAUCUCUUUCUAGCAAGAAGAGACAAGAUUUUGUGCAUUUGUACAAAUGUUAAUAUCACUGCAAUUCCAAUAUAAUAAAGCACUCAAAUGCAAAUAA